AUCCGCCCCGCCUCCAACUUGCUCGAGCAGGGCUGGGUAGACCGGCGCGCUCCCGGGGACGGUGGGGGGGGCAGUCCCGGUUUCGGCCAUCGCUGGGGUGGGCUCGGAGCGGCCGCACCGGGCAGCAACCCCACUCCCACUCGGAGGCCCCCUGCCCUCUCCCCCACUUCCCCCCGGCCCAUGGUGCGAGGCUGGGAGCCGCCGCCCGGGCUGGACUGCGCUAUCUCUGAAGGGCACAAAUCAGAAGGCACCAUGCCUCCUAAUAAAGAGGCCAGCGGUCUCAGUAGUUCACCAGCGGGGCUCAUCUGCCUCCCUCCAAUCUCUGAGGAGCUACAGCUUGUGUGGACGCAAGCAGCCCAGACCAGUGAGCUAGACAGCAAUGAACACCUGCUCAAAACCUUCAGCUACUUUCCCUAUCCCAGCCUAGCAGACAUUGCCCUUCUCUGCCUACGUUAUGGGUUGCAGAUGGAGAAAGUCAAGACUUGGUUUAUGGCCCAGCGCCUCCGCUGUGGUAUUAGCUGGUCAUCUGAAGAAAUAGAAGAGACUCGAGCCCGAGUAGUCUACCGUCGGGACCAACUCCAUUUCAAAUCCCUUCUCUCUUUUACUCAUCAUGCGGGACGGCCCCCAGAGGAGGUGCCUCCUCCUCCAGUGCCAGCUCCAGAGCAAGUUGGUAUUGGAAUAGGUCCUCCAACUCUUAGCAAGCCUACCCAGACGAAAGGAUUGAAGGUAGAGCCUGAGGAGCCCUCUCAGAUGCCACCACUGCCACAGAGUCACCAGAAAUUAAAGGAGUCCCUGAUGACACCUGGCAGUGGAGCAUUCCCCUACCAAUCAGAUUUUUGGCAACAUCUUCAAAGCAGUGGCCUCUCAAAGGAGCAGGCAGGCAGGGGUCCCAACCAGUCACAUGGCAUAGGUACUGCUUCCUGGAACCACUCCACAACCGUCCCCCAGCCACAAGCUCGGGAUAAACCCCCACCAAUUGCAUUAAUUGCCAGUAGUUGUAAGGAGGAGUCAGCAUCUAGUGUUACUCCCUCUUCUUCCUCUACCUCUUCUUCUUUCCAGGUACUGGCUAAUGGAGCUACUGCCGCCUCUAAACCCCUCCAGCCACUAGGCUGUGUCCCACAGUCAGUGUCACCCAGUGAACAGGCAUUACCCCCACAUCUGGAACCAGCCUGGCCCCAAGGGCUACGGCAUAACUCAGUACCAGGUAGAGUUGGCCCCACAGAGUACCUUUCCCCAGAUAUGCAACGCCAGCGAAAGACCAAGCGCAAAACCAAAGAGCAGCUGGCUAUCCUUAAAUCCUUUUUUUUACAGUGCCAGUGGGCACGGCGUGAGGAUUACCAAAAGUUAGAACAGAUCACUGGUUUACCUCGGCCUGAGAUCAUUCAGUGGUUUGGUGACACACGCUAUGCCUUGAAGCAUGGGCAACUAAAGUGGUUUCGGGACAACGCAGUACCUGGUGCCCCUAGUUUCCAAGACCCAGCAAUUCCUACACCACCACCAUCAACCCGCUCCUUGAACGAAAGGGCUGAGACACCACCUCUGCCGAUCCCUCCACCCCCACCGGAUAUACAACCCUUGGAGAGGUACUGGGCAGCCCACCAACAGCUACGGGAAACUGAUAUCCCUCAAUUGAGUCAGGCAUCAAGGCUUAGCACCCAGCAGGUGCUGGAUUGGUUUGACUCUCGAUUACCUCAGCCAGCUGAGGUGGUAGUUUGUCUAGAUGAAGAAGAGGAAGAGGAGGAGGAAGAACUGCCAGAAGAUGAUGAGGAAGAGGAGGAGGAGGAGGAGGAAGAUGAUGAUGAUGAUGAUGAUGAUGUGAUCAUACAAGACUGAGUGGGGAGCUGGGGGAGGGGAGGUCUGUUACUGAAAGAUGAACCAACUUAGUAACUGUUUAAACAAAGAAACCACAUUUUUAAAAUUACCUUGUGGCAGAGAACUAAAAAGCUUUGUGUUCUUCAGGGUGGGUGGCAGGGGGAUAUAGUGAGGGUGGACCAGGGAGAAUGACCAUAGGGCACUAAGUAAGGCUGGGAUUGGAUCAGCAGAAAUCCAACCCUCUAACCUUAGGGUAGGGAGUGCUAAGGAUCUGGGGAAACCAUGGGCUGGGAAGCUGCUCUUGCUCUCCUCGUGUCUGCUGUUUUUUUCCCUUGGUGUACUAUACAGAGGCCAGAUGUUGGCACCACCUCUCCAGGAGGAUUGGAAAGGAGGAGUAAAGGAUUCUGAUUUGAUUGAUGAUUCCAGUGCAUCCCCAAUCCCACCAUCUUACCUGGAAUAUAAGGCUGCCUUGUACCCCUUUUCUGAGCACAAGUCUGUGCGUAAUGCAACUGACUCUCUUACUUUUUUCUUAGUAACUGAUCAUUUCCUAGACAACCAAGAUUCUCAAUAAGUCCCAGUCUCAUCACAAAUAUUAAUAUUUCCUUUUCCUCAUACCAACUUGACUAUGUUUCACCCGCUUCAUGACUAAAUCACAGGUGGCAGAAUUUUUCAGUUCUUUUUUUUUUUUUUGAGGUGGAGUCUUGCUCUGUCGCCCAGGCUGUAGUGCAAUGGCGCAAUCUCAGCUCACUGCAAGCUCCGCCUCCCAGGUUCAUGCCAUUCUCCUGCCUCAGCCUCCCGAGUAGCUGGGACUACAGGCACCUGCCACCACACCCGGCUACUUUUUUAUAUUUUUAGUAGAGACGGGUUUCAUCAUGUUAGCCAGGAUGGUCUUGAUCUCCUGACCUCAUGAUCCGCCCACCUUGGCCUCCCAAAGUGCUGGGAUUAUAGGCAUGAGCCACCGUGCCCGGCUAUUUUCAGUUCUUAUGCUGUGACCACUUUGCCUUGUAGCUUUUUCUAUCUUUCCAAAAUCCUCACUCUGUUCAUUGUUUGUCUCAGGGAAAAUCUUCCCCCACCGAGCUUGUAAAAAACUUUAAUAAUUGGGUGGAGAAUAAUUUAGAAUGGAUAUUUAUUGGAGGUGGUAAUUAGGGAAGAUGUCCUUUUAAACAGUAGAAUUGUGUUACAAAGGGGUGAAAGAGAGGGAAUAGUUUCUCCUUGUUGAAGGGCAGUGAAGGUAGGUUUCAGGUUUGGUUUUACAAACCUGUUAACUACCUCCUGUCCAGCUUGACAGAGACUAAUUUUUCAUCUUUUUGCUGUCAAUUUGUUUCCAGAAAAGAGACUUUUCCCUCUCUUGAUAGGAUCUGUCUUAGGGACAGAGGGACCAUCGUCUUUAAGUGAAUUAAUUAUUGAUGUUUUAGAAUGGUUUUCAUCAGUUGGGAUCAGCUAUAUGGCAAAUAGGUAUCAUCAAUGAGUUAACCAUCUAAAAAUAAAAGAGUGGAAGCCCUAAAAUGCUAGAAUAAUAAUAAAAAGGCCAAAAAUAAAAUUGUUUCUCUCUCAACCACUUUGCCACUCCUAUGGUUUAGGGAUUAAUGGAACCAAAUCCAUUAACAUUCUAACUCAGCAUACUUUUAACUUAUUGUUUGGAGGGGCAGGACUUAUUGAGGUAAAUUAAAAGAACAAAAACUGUAAAAAGGAAGUAGUUCAGCAUCUAUCGCCAGCCAGGUUGUUUCUCAGCCAUCAAAUGAUAAUGACUAAAAUUUCUGAGGCUUCAGGAGUAACAGAGAUACAACAGUCUUGGAGGUAACUCCAUUUGCUACAGGACAGGCCCUUGCCUAAAAGAGAAGGUAUCUAGAAAUGCCUUUAAAAUAAAUUCAGAGUACCAGAAAGGGUAUGGGGAUCCUAGUUCAGAUACAAGAUCAUUCCCAAGACCUAAUUUAUUUCUGGCAGAUGCCUGCUAUUUUCUGUUUUUCCAGUAUUUUUGCUUAAGGCCAGCUUGUGAGUGGCUAACCUAUUUAAUUCGUCAUUUCUGCCUUUUAAAACCCAAAGUAGAAUACAUGUUUGAUCUCAGUGAUAGUGUUGUUCGCCCAUUCCACCAUUCUAGAGCUUGUAAAAGUGAUAGAAUUGUAGCAAUAAAAGGGCAUCGUCUUUAUUUUACUAUCUAUAUACUAAGCUGAAAAUCAGUGUCUCCAACAGUUGUUUUCAAUAGAAAGGAAAAUUAACAUUUAAUAGUAACUAAGCAUAGAGGAAAUAAUAGACAAAUAAAAAAGUAUAAUAAGGAAAAGAACAGAGAUAUUGCUCGUUAACAUUGGCAAUGGGACAGUAUAUCCAAAGCUAAAAAUGAAAUCCAGAAAUGAAACAGUGAUGAGUAUAUGAUCCAUCACAAUCCCCAUUCCCAACUCCCAACCAAGCAUGAUGCCAAGAAUUAUUUUUUUGACCUUUGUUCCAAAUUGUAGGAAAUGAGGGGAGCUACCAGUGUCUUCUGGAAGAGAUAUAAACAUCUUCCUGAAGCACUAGCCUUUUGUAAGACCUGACCACUGUCCUGGGAGGUGAUAAGGGUGAAUAGGGUAAAGAUGGGGGGAGCAUAAGGUACAGAGUGAAACUAGGAAACAAUGCAGGGAUACAUUUUCCAGGGCCAUCACCCCUAAUGCGUACUGGAAGCUACAGUCCAUCCUUCAGCAGCAUGUAUAGAUCAGAUCUUGAAGAUGAUCUAUCUAGAAGUGGUCCAUGCUUCUCUCCCACUGGGUAAUCCCAUAUGCCUCCGUUGUUGGUAGAGAGUCUGCAGCAGAGGACAAGAAGGUAGAUGUGGGUGUUUAUAACAGCAAAAAGGGCAAGCAAGUCUCUCUGACCUGUUGUAUGAAGCUUAUCGAGACAGACACCACUGCUUUUGCUUCCCCAUAGUUUUCUUCAUUGCAUGAUAACUAACUUUUCCAAACUAGGAUUUGCUACAUCUAGUGUGACAAUCUCUGGAACAUUUCAGUAGCUUAUGGUGAUAAUAAUAAGGAUGAAUAUUUGAAAAUUAAACUAUUUUGGAAAAUCUGGGACAUAUGACUACCACACCCAGAGAUGACUACCAGGGAGGCAGAGUUCUUAGGCCUCUGAGGAGGUGGCAUUUCCUUCAAUAACUUUAAAAUUUUUUCACAUUUUCGGUUGUUUGUUUGUUUGUUUGUUUGUUGUUUU